GAACCGUUUGGCUCUUUCCCUUAGUAACAGCUUUUACCUUCUGCCUCAAUUCCUCUCCCCGCUCGCGCCCUUCCCCCGCGCGCCGCCUCCCCCCGCCGCCGGCCGCGUGCGCCCCCGCCCCUCCCCCCGCGGCGGGAGCACCUCCGCUCGCCACCUGGGGACCCGCGCCGCGCUCCCCGCCCCCGCCCGCCCGGCGCCCAUCCCCCGCGCCCUCCGCUCGCUGGGGUUAUAAUUGCCUCUCACCCCCCGGAGGGGUUAUUUUGGGGGUGGUUGGAGGCGGUGGCGGCGGCGGCGAGGAGGGGAAUUUCCUUGUGCCUCCAUUCCCGGGAGGGGGGAGCGGCGUUGGAGGCCACCGUUUCCAGAUAUUUUCCUCUUCUGGACCCUAUCUAGAAGAAGUAUUCCUUAGACAAUUUCCGGCUUCUUUUCUCUCAUGAAGAGGAGGUAAGAUUUUUGUUCUCACACUUAUCUGCUUCCCAAAAUAUCCCCCCCGUUCUCAUUAAGUUCUGACCACUCCUUCCUCUCAUCUCAUUUAAUUCUUAUUCAUAUCUAGAAUUGUGUUUUAGGUACAAUAGUAGGCAUAAGUCACAGACAUACUGUCAUUUAUUCCUGUGCAUUUACAAUAGAAGGUAUUGAAAAAAUUCAGCUUAGUGUCUUCAUAGUUCUAGCUUUAUGCAUUUUCACAGACAUUUAUCCUUUGCCUCCUCUUUGUCUUCUGCUGAAGAAUAGUGAACACAGUAGGGAAAAAAAAACCACAAAACCAAGACCAGGUGUUCUUAAGCAAAGAAGUUCUGGUUUGUGUUUUGUUAUUUUUCCCUAGUCAGGUAUUUUAAAUUCGUAAUGGUGGGUGUAUAGCCCUAGAUACAUUGUAAGCUUUGCUGGAUAUUUACAAAUUGUUGCCUAAACUGUAGAAGGGCUUAAGUCAUUAGACAUUCUAUUUUAGUGACAUUUUUCUGUUUUUCUGUAUCAUGUGUCUUGGAAAAACUUUGAAGUUCUUUGAUGUUAAUUUUGUAAGAAUGUGUGUCUGAAAAUAUUUUGACUGAAUAGACUCUGGGUUACAGUUAAGAAUUUCUUUGAUUUGGCACAUCUUCUCUUUAGCAUUUCAUAGCUUUUAUCAUGGCCUGCAUAUACAACAUGUCAAUUAUAAUGCCUGAUAGGUCUCCUAGGAGUUGUAGCUUCACAAUAUAUAGGAGGCAUCAGGCACAAAUCGAUACUGCAGAGAAAAAAUUAGAGUAACUAAAACAUAAAUGACGUAUUUUGUGAAUAAGGAAGUGUUCUAGGUAUGCCUUCCAGUAGUAAGCGGACAACACCAAGAUAUAAGGCACGUCUUCAUACAUCAUUGUCUGUACACAGAACAUCGAGCAUACAGGAAGCUUCCUGAGUAUCUUGCUGUCUCUCAAUUGAAAUACAAACCAACUCUGGCUCUGACCAUCCUACUUUAAUAUUGCAACCCAGGGGUUCCUCUUUCACCUCUCUUCCCCCCAACUUCUGAAUCCCUUUACCCUGCUUGGACUUUUUCUUUUUUCAUAGCAUUUAUGAUUGUAACAUUACUUAUUAAUCAAAAUUCUGCUGGAAUUUAAACUGUGAGAGAGCAGGGAUCUGUGUUUUAUUUACUGAUGUAUUUUAGUAAGUUUUGUCCCCAGUGGGUGAAUUAAUAGUAACUCGAUGUAAAGGGCUAACUUUUAAUGUUAACAAUCUCUAGUAGAAAGGUUAAUUACAAUUUGUUUUUUCUUCCUUCUUCCUUUCUUUCCCCACCUCUUCUUUCUUCCCAUAGUUCUGUUGUCUACUGCAGGACAAAUCUUACAAUCAUCCCAAAAUACAAAAACAAAACAACCUUCUGUUUAGUCUUGGAGGUAAACAUAGGCUUUAAAUUACAUUUCUUCCUAUUCUCUUAAAGGGGACUUGCUUGAUAGUUUGUAUUUUCUUGAGUAACUAAUGCAUUUCUAAUGGAGAGAGUUCAUUUAGUGUGCAGGUUCUUUGUUUCUGAUUGAAUGUUUGGUUGCUUUCAUAUUCAGUUUAUGUUCAAUUAAAAAAUUGGGAAAAGGUAUGAAAUUGACAAUUUUAAAUGUAAUUUUGUUUAUAUAUUAACUUGUUUUUAAAAAUUAAUUACAAAUAUACAAUUUACUUGUUUUUUCCCCAUAUUUAUCUGUGAAUUAGAUUAUGAUUUAGGAUUGUUAGAAAAUGUGAAAAGAAAACAUGUUUGACAAUAACAUUUUCAUCUCUAUUAUAGAAGUGAUUUUUGGUAUCCAGAUAUCCUUAUCCCAUCAAAAAGCUAAAAUGCAAGCUCAUUUUCUGUUAAUUUUUAAGAUGGGCAUAACAUUUCUUCUCAUCGCUGCUUGGUGAACAUUAGCUAGUAUUGCCACAACUUAUGGCCAGUGUUUUCUGUUUCUUCCUUCCUUCUAUUUGCUCUGGCAAAGAGGACGCAUUUCCAGGACCAGUCUCAGCUAGCCCAGUGUCUUUAUUGUCUGUUUCUUUGUUGUUUGCAUUAAUAAAAAUACCAUUAGUAUUUUUUAAACUCAUGGAAAUUCAUAAUUCAAACAAUUUUUUUGCUUAGGGAGUUGAUUCUUUUUGUUCUUUUAAUACUAUACUAUUUUUAACCUUUUUGCUCCCUUUUAAACUAUACAUGCAGUUAUAAUUAACUGAUAUUAGUAUUACUUCUGUGCGAAAAUGCCUUUAGGCAUUCAAUAGGAUUAUAAAUCCUAGUUUAUUUUCUUUACAAUAAGCCAAACACUAUGUUCAUACUUGUUAUCAAGCUGUCUAAUACACUAUAUAGAUGAAGACACUGAGGGCUUGCUUACAGUUGUAUGGAUAUGAUGUGAAAGAGCUGAGUUUUUAAACAGAACAGAAAGCCUUAUUCUUUCCAUUCUUACCCCCACUGUCUUUUAAGUUUCUAAAGAUGGCAGAGGAAUGUUGAAGUUUAAUACUUAUAAUUUUCUUAAUGAACUUCAUUAUUAUAUAUAGGGCCACAUAAGAUACUAUGUUUGAAUUCCUUAGAAAAUUUCCUUUUCAUAGAAUGGUUAUAUAUUUUUAGUAGGCAGUGUUUAAAUAGUAAGUGUUUUUGCUUGGUCUGUUAAUUUAUUUGAUUUAAAAAAAUGUUUACCUCAUUUAACCUAAAAGCUUCUUUGCUUUAUCCUGGAUCUGUAGAAAUUUGGAUGGUUCUGGGAAUUGCUUCAGAGUCAACAAACUAUGACCUGUGGACCAUAUCUGCAUCAACAACAGCAACUUGUGAUUGGCGGUGACCGGAUAUUCAGUUGCACAUCCCCACAUCAAUGCACUGCCAAUGGAUUUUCUCAUUCAGCAUUUACCUUUGGUAUAGAAAGCCAUAUCAGUCAGUCCAAUAUAAAUGGUGCCCUCGUCCCACCCGCUGCAUUGAUUUCUAUCAUCCAGAAAGGUCUACAGUAUGUAGAAGCAGAAGUUAGUAUUAAUGAGGAUGGUACCUUGUUUGAUGGUCGACCAAUAGAGUCUCUGUCCCUGAUAGAUGCCGUAAUGCCUGAUGUAGUACAAACAAGACAACAAGCUUAUAGAGAUAAGCUUGCACAGCAACAGGCAGCAGCUGCUGCAGCUGCCGCAGCUGCAGCCAGCCAACAAGGAUCUGCAAAAAAUGGAGAAAACACAGCAAAUGGGGAGGAGAAUGGAGCACAUACUAUAGCAAAUAAUCAUACUGAUAUGAUGGAAGUGGAUGGGGAUGUUGAAAUCCCUCCUAAUAAAGCUGUUGUGUUGCGGGGCCAUGAAUCUGAAGUUUUUAUCUGUGCCUGGAACCCUGUUAGUGAUCUCCUAGCAUCAGGGUCUGGAGACUCAACAGCAAGAAUAUGGAAUCUUAGUGAGAACAGCACCAGUGGCUCUACACAGUUAGUACUUAGACAUUGUAUACGAGAAGGAGGGCAAGAUGUUCCAAGCAACAAGGAUGUCACAUCUCUAGAUUGGAAUAGUGAAGGUACACUUCUAGCAACUGGUUCCUAUGAUGGGUUUGCCAGAAUAUGGACUAAAGAUGGUAACCUUGCUAGCACCUUAGGGCAGCAUAAAGGCCCUAUAUUUGCAUUAAAAUGGAAUAAGAAAGGAAAUUUCAUCCUAAGUGCUGGAGUAGACAAGACUACAAUUAUUUGGGACGCACAUACUGGUGAAGCCAAGCAACAGUUUCCUUUUCAUUCAGCACCAGCAUUGGAUGUUGAUUGGCAGAGCAACAACACCUUUGCUUCUUGUAGUACAGAUAUGUGCAUUCAUGUCUGUAAAUUAGGACAAGACAGACCUAUUAAAACAUUCCAAGGACAUACGAAUGAAGUAAAUGCUAUCAAAUGGGACCCAACUGGCAAUCUCUUGGCCUCCUGUUCUGACGACAUGACUUUAAAGAUAUGGAGUAUGAAACAAGACAAUUGUGUCCAUGAUUUGCAAGCACAUAAUAAAGAAAUUUAUACUAUCAAAUGGAGUCCAACAGGACCAGGGACUAAUAAUCCAAAUGCCAACCUUAUGUUAGCAAGUGCAUCCUUUGAUUCUACUGUUAGGUUAUGGGAUGUAGACCGAGGGAUAUGCAUCCAUACCUUGACAAAACACCAAGAGCCUGUGUACAGUGUAGCUUUCAGUCCUGAUGGCAGGUAUCUGGCAAGUGGUUCUUUUGACAAAUGUGUACACAUCUGGAACACGCAGACAGGUGCUCUAGUUCACAGCUAUAGGGGAACAGGUGGAAUAUUUGAAGUUUGCUGGAAUGCAGCAGGAGACAAAGUUGGAGCCAGUGCAUCAGAUGGUUCAGUUUGUGUAUUAGACCUUCGGAAAUAGCGCUACUAGUUGGAAGCCAUGGACCGACUAUGAAUGUGUACAUAGCCAAAAUGACUGUCCCUGACCCAUGUACUGCUAUAGUCCCACUUGAACCAUGGCCAGUCCACUACAGCCAAAUCUAAAAGAAAUAUAUACAUACAGUGUAUAUAAACAAAAUUGCACCCUGAAGAUGACAGAGUUUUGUCACAGCUUGUGAAUUCUGUUCACCAAGUGCUGGAAUCUAAUCUGCUGUGCCCCUAAAAUAGCAUUUAGAAGUUUUGGAUAUGAAAAACAGAAGAGAGAAAAAUAUACAUUAUAAAAGCAGAACAUACAUGUACCAGUUUUUGGAUACUAAAUGACAGCCUUGUUUCUCCCCUUUGAAUCAGCAGACACCAUGGAUUAUAUUCUUUUUUUCCCUUCAGUAGUGAGCAGUUUGUAUGUACAGAGAAAAUGGACUUACAAAAACUUGCAGCAGUAGUUUGUUCUUGCUUUAAAAUUUCGUUUUUGGUUUAGAUUAUGGAUGCAUGAAGUAAGGGAGUGAAUCAGUUUCUUGUUUAUAUUUUUUUCACCUUUUAAACAAAAAAUUCUUUAAAAUAUUUUAAUGCAUUCUUUUGAAGAGGUAGAUGUUUGGUACAUUUUAUGGCUCCCAGAGCAUAUAUUCAGUUGGUGCAUGUUGUGGAAGGGGGAAUUGGAAAUUAAAUGAAAACCUAUGACUUUGGUCAUGUCAAUCUGUAAGACACAUCAGUAAAAGGGUAUUAUGCUCUGUUGGUUUUGUUUUUUUGUUUUGCUUUUUUUUUUUUUUUUUCUUUUUUGUUUUUUGGUGAUGUGGCUUAAAUGCAAUAGUUUCUUUUUUGGGACAUAUUUCUGCCAAUUAAAGACUAGAAGGGCACAACUUUUUUUUUAAUUACCAUAGAGAAGAUACAUUAAAAAAAAUCUUCUGAUGUUUUGUAGCCAUAACUAAAUUAUGGUAAAAAUGUGCACUAUUGUGAAAAGGAGCAACGUAGUUUUGGGUUUUUUGUUGUUUGUUUGUUUUGCUUUGUUUUUUAAGAGAUUAAAAUGUUUCUGGAUAAGGAUUAGCUUCUCGAAGUGUCCAUCAUUCUGUGUAGAAGCUUAAAUAUGUAAUGUAACCAAACUCCAGUAUUAAAAAUCUCUCAUGUUGUUUUCUUUAUACAAAGCAAGAUAACGGCAUAUAACACUGCCAUUACAUGGCAAAAUGUUUGCUACCUUAGUUUAAAAAACAAUCUCAAACAAAAGACUUGCUUCAAGGUGUUUUUAAAUAGCAGUGAUUCAGAAUUUUUUUUAAUGAAAGUAUAAUUGCACUAACCUUCUUCCUGCUGCUCUGAUUCUGCAUUUGUGGUACUUGUGACUACGUUUUUUCAAAUAUAGAUAGAUUUAAGCUGCUAAUUUUUUUUUUUUUAGUAAUCACUACUAUAUCAUGUCUUUUACUCUGUUUAUAAUAUCAAGUAUUUUCUUAAAGAUAUAGAUAUUAAACCUUGUGCUCAUGCAACUUAGAGUAACAUAUACAGACAAAUGAUUGCAUGAGGCCAUGUUUAUAUGUGUGACUAAUAAGGCUUGUCAUGAUUAACAUAAUCCAGGUAUGUCAUUUCUGAAGAGAAUAGUCAUCAAAUUUAUAUCUCGAAGAUUUUAAUUAAGGAAUUGCUUAUUGUUGAGCUUAGCAAAUUAAUAACACUAUUUCUGUCACUAAUUAUUUUGAGGCCUUUUAGUACUAAAAUUUUAACCUGUGUUCUAAGUAGAAACUGAUUUAACCCAAGUAAUGCAGCUUUGAUUGAUUUCAGCAUUCGUUGCUUUGCUAUUUUUACAAAACAGCAUUGAUUGAAGCAAGUCUUGGUUUUACUAAGGUAGGGUAGCAUUUGCUAUUGGUAAAGAGAAUAAAUACACUUAAUUUCACAAUACAUUGUUAUAUGUACCCCAGUUGUUGUUAGUGGGGACUAUGAUACUGUAAUAAUAUUUUUAAAAAUUUACAUCAAGAGAGGCAGUCAUUCACGAUGGUUUUGUGCCAGCUCUUUUUAGGGUUUUGGAUCACAUUAGAGAUAUUUAGAACAUAUUACCCUGUGACUUACGUAGGAAACCUAAUAUGCUGAGUAUCUGGCACUUGAAUUCCUGCUUUUAUUGCUGGAGGUCCACAUCUGUGGUUGACCUCUGUUAUUGUUUAAAAAAAAUAAAUAAAAAUUAAAAAAAUCUGUGCAAUAAUUUUAAAAUGUGCUCCCAGGAAUAGACACAAAUGUUUUGAGUAUCUUUUAAGCUGCAUUUUCCUUUAGUGAUGCAUUUGUCAAUUGCACUGAAUUUAAAUCUGAAAGUCAGAGGUGAUUAUUGAUAGUACUUUUGUAUUUUGAUAUGGACAGUUUAUUCAUUUGCAUACAGUUAUUGACUUUUUCCCAGCUGAUUAAAAGAUAGUCAAGAAAUUCUGCAAUAUAGCUGCCAAAAUAGACAGCUACAUUUUUAUGAUAUUGUCAUCUUUUCUGUUUUUUUUUUCUUUUUUUUCUUUAGCUAUUUUACUUAAGCAUAAUAGCCACAAUAGGACAUAUAAAAGAUUAUAAAUACAGAGCUUUAUUAUCCUGACGUCUUGGGUCUUUUAAGUAUAUACUUUUCUGAAAGGUAUCCAUUUUGUAGGCUUGGGUUCUUCAUGAGCAUACGAUUGUUUAUUUUUGCUGCUGUUCUCAACAUCAUCAUUGCCUGCUGAUGUGCCACGAUGCUGCUCCAAUAGACAGCAAUAAGAUUGUCUCUAAUUUGAGCAGUAACAUGAUUGCAAGAGACCAAGUUUCACAGCUUGUAAAGUUCUGUAUUUGGGAUUCUUGCUUAUUUUUCCGCCUGUGUUUUUCUGAGAACUUAUUCCUGAUGAUCAAUUGAAUCCAGUAGUUUUUCUAUGCUAUUUGUUGUUGUAUAAGCUACUGUAAGAAACUUAUCAUAAGGAAAAAUAGAAAGGAAAACUUGAAUCAAUACUCAUUGAUUAAAAUGGAAUAAAGAAAGAGCAGCUGCCACUUUUAAACAACAUAAAGGAAUAUCUUUUUUUGUCUCCGUGUAGGAAAUCCCAUAAGUUCUUAUAUUUGUUCCAGUUCCCAUUUCCUGCCAUUGACCAGAUAACAUCAUUGACUUUCAAAUGACUUUUAGAAGUGAUAACUCUUAAUUUCCUAAUAGAUACUAGAUUGUAUUGAAUUCUGUUUUAAUUAUUCUCUAGGUAAGUAUGUUUUAGGAUUAAAUACCUUUUACAGAUACUGAAAGUGCCUCCUUUUGUGGUGUAAAAAACAAAUUAUGGUGCAAAAAGUAAUCACUAGAUUGAAAUACAUGAAGGUUUUUUGCUUUUUGACAUACGAAAAUGUCAAGAGAAAGGCCAAAGAUUUGUACUUUUUCACUUACAAAGCACUCCUUUUUCCCUUAAACUUCUUUCUGUCAAAUUAGAUUUAAUGAGAGAGUACUAUUUUUAAGGAGCUAUCUGUUUAUGUAGAAUGAUUUUGUUAAGAGUAAUGUAAACUAUUAUUGAGUAGAGGCCUAAAGAGGACUGUGCAUUUUUGCUAUUUAAAGGAAUCACAAAUGAUCAUACUUAAGUGAGCAAAAAUGACAAGUUUUACUAGCUAAGUAGAGAAAUAAAUCUCAAAUGCAGCGCUACAAUUUUCAUUAUCUUAAGUACAUUGUACAUUUCUACAGAACCUGUGAUUAUUCUCGCAUGAUAAGGAUGGUACUUGCAUAUGGUGAAUUACUACUGUUGACAGUUUCCGCAGAAAUCCUAUUUCAGUGGACCAACAUUGUGGCAUGGCAGCAAAUGCCAACAUUUUGUGGAAUAGCAGCAAAUCUACAAGAGACCCUGGUUGGUUUUUCGUUUUGUUUUCUUUGUUUUUUCCCCCUUCUCCUGAAUCAGCAGGGAUGGAAGGAGGGUAGGGAAGUUAUGAAUUACUCCUUCCAGUAGUAGCUCUGAAGUGUCACAUUUAAUAUCAGUUUUUUUUAAACAUGAUUCUAGUUAAAUGUAGAAGAGAGAAGAAAGAGGAAGUGUUCACUUUUUUAAUACACUGAUUUAGAAAUUUGAUGUCUUAUAUCAGUAGUUCUGAGGUAUUGAUAGCUUGCUUUAUUUCUGCCUUUACGUUGACAGUGUUGAAGCAGGGUGAAUAACUAGGGCAUAUAUUUUUUUUUUUUUUGUAAGCUGUUUCAUGAUGUUUUCUUUGGAAUUUCCGGAUAAGUUCAGGAAAACAUUCUGCAUGUUGUAUCUAGUCUGAUGUACUUAUCCAUCUCAUUACAAACAAAAACACACAGACUGCAUUUGUAGCUCUGUAAUCCUUGAAUACGGAAGUAAAUUUUCUUCUUUCCUGACUUUGACAUUGUAGCUAUACUGUUUCCAUUUUUGUUUUUACAAAUCCUUUGGGUCUAAUUCUGUGAGCCUACCUAUAGCACUGGAUUAAAAUGUCUGCAUCAUUUCUUUAGUUAUCCAGUUAACUUUAAAACUGUUGUAAAAGUGUAAACCAGCCCAUGACAGGUUUUUGUACAUGUUAAAGAACUUCAUUGUUCAGUUUUCAUGAUUAUUGUGUAAGGAAGACUGAUGUAGAUGUUCUGUGCUGUCCUGGACCAUGUUAAUUACACUUACGACGUAUUUUAGUUCCACAUCACAAUGAUUUGUCCCCAGUGACCCUUUUAUCCUUUCUAGGCACAUUUCUUGUUGUUGUUGUUGUUGCAGUUCCCCUUUGCAUUGUAUUGCUUUGACAACUGUAAUUUGAAUCAGAUCUGAAAGAGGUCCAGAAUAAAAUAUAUUUUGAUAUUAUGUUGGCUGUGUACAUAUAUAAAACCUUUGAUGUCUAUGUAGUUUAUAUAGACUAUUUACUAGUCAGGUAAAGAGAGAGGGAUGGUAUUUCUUGUUUACAGUUUGUUUACAUUUUAAUUGCUUUUACUUCUCCAGUGUUCUAUUGUAGAAUAAACCUUUUUUUCCAAGUUAGCCUUCAUAACCUAUAACACAUUCAUUCUCUCCCAUACUGGUGUUACUGAUUAAUAACUGCCAUCAGAACCCAAACCACUGUUUUUCAUAAACGUAUUGUUUCCCAAGAUAUAUACUUUAAGCCCAUAAUAAAAUUACAAAUUUUACUAUUUUUAUUACUUCUUGCAGGAGAUAAGAUUUUUUUAAAUGAAGGGGUUAUUUACUAUUUUUAUUAAAGUAUAAUAGAGCAUCUAAUCAGCUAAGGGAUUGUAAUUUUUAAUUCUUUUGAAAAAUAAAUAUUGUAUUUAAAAGACGUUAUUUCACAGAAGCUGAAAAAGAGACCUUAGAUAACAUUUGUUUGGUUAGCCACACGGUUGAGCACAAAACAAUGUGUAGAUGUGUUGAAGAUUAGGGCAGGAGGCUCAACUUCUCGGUGACCUUUUUUUGCUUCACAACAAGCCAAUUAUAGUUGAAUCAUUUUCUCUCUUAGCUAGUUGUUACUACAAACUUUAUAAGAAAAACAACUAGACACCUUCUAGUUUUAAUUAAUACCAACUCCUUUAGAGUUAGAGACUUUUUAAAAAGAAUCAUUGAGCAUAUUUUCUUUUUUUUUUUUUUAAGAAUUUACACUCUCUAGGUCUUCUAUUUUUCCUGUUUAUUUCCUUAAACAGAAAUAAAUUCAAGCAUAGUUUUAUGUUUUAUUAGAAAUAAGCCACUGCAGUUGCUAGAACUGACAUGCUUUCAUUUUCAAGGGGUUAACUUUUAUUGCAUGGCAUAGAUUAUUAGUAAUAUCCUGCAUUGUAUACUUUUCCAAAAAGGGUUGGACUCCUAAGGAUUAGAAUCCUUAUAAGCUUGAGGGAAAGCUGAAACUAAUUUGAACAGUAAUAGAAGGGAUUAUUUUUAAUUUCAUAGUUAACACUUUACAAUGGAUUAGAUUUAUUACCUAGUAUAAUCCGUAGCAGAUCAGAUCAAAGUUUACUGUUUUACCAAUAUAUUCAUUUGAAAAAAUACAGUGGAGGAAAAGACACUUUAGAUGGUAGUUUUAUGGUGCUUUUCUCUGCUGUACCAAAGUGCUUUGUCAUCAAUGAAAUGUUAACCCUAUGCUACUUUUUCUGCAUGCUUCUUAAAUGUCAUCUUAAUGCUUAAUUGUCCUAACUUGUAAUAUUUUUGUAUUAAAUUUUUUUAGGAGUUCCUUGUAAUUUCUUUACAAUUUAAAAUAUAUUAAACACAAAGUGUUUAGUAAAGUACAGAAGACAAUUA